CAUUUCGCCAGCUCCUCUGGGGGUGACAGGCAAGUGAGACGUGCUCAGAGCUCCGAUGCCAAGGCCAGGGACCAUGGCGCUGUGUCUGCUGACCUUGGUCCUCUCGCUCUUGCCCCCACAAGCUGCUGCAGAACAGGACCUCAGUGUGAACAGGGCUGUGUGGGAUGGAGGAGGGUGCAUCUCCCAAGGGGACGUCUUGAACCGUCAGUGCCAGCAGCUGUCUCAGCACGUUAGGACAGGUUCUGCGGCAAACACCGCCACAGGUACAACAUCUACAAAUGUCGUGGAGCCAAGAAUGUAUUUGAGUUGCAGCACCAACCCUGAGAUGACCUCGAUUGAGUCCAGUGUGACUUCAGACACUCCUGGUGUCUCCAGUACCAGGAUGACACCAACAGAAUCCAGAACAACUUCAGAAUCUACCAGUGACAGCACCACACUUUUCCCCAGUUCUACUGAAGACACUUCAUCUCCUACAACUCCUGAAGGCACCGACGUGCCCAUGUCAACACCAAGUGAAGAAAGCAUUUCAUCAACAAUGGCUUUUGUCAGCACUGCACCUCUUCCCAGUUUUGAGGCCUACACAUCUUUAACAUAUAAGGUUGAUAUGAGCACACCUCUGACCACUUCUACUCAGGCAAGUUCAUCUCCUACUACUCCUGAAAGCACCACCAUACCCAAAUCAACUAACAGUGAAGGAAGCACUCCAUUAACAAGUAUGCCUGCCAGCACCAUGAAGGUGGCCAGUUCAGAGGCUAUCACCCUUUUGACAACUCCUGUUGAAAUCAGCACACCUGUGACCAUUUCUGCUCAAGCCAGUUCAUCUCCUACAACUGCUGAAGGUCCCAGCCUGUCAAACUCAGCUCCUAGUGGAGGAAGCACUCCAUUAACAAGAAUGCCUCUCAGCGUGAUGCUGGUGGUCAGUUCUGAGGCUAGCACCCUUUCAACAACUCCUGCUGCCACCAACAUUCCUGUGAUCACUUCUACUGAAGCCAGUUCAUCUCCUACAACGGCUGAAGGCACCAGCAUACCAACCUCAACUUAUACUGAAGGAAGCACUCCAUUAACAAGUACGCCUGCCAGCACCAUGCCGGUUGCCACUUCUGAAAUGAGCACACUUUCAAUAACUCCUGUUGACACCAGCACACUUGUGACCACUUCUACUGAACCCAGUUCACUUCCUACAACUGCUGAAGCUACCAGCAUGCUAACCUCAACUCUUAGUGAAGGAAGCACUCCAUUAACAAAUAUGCCUGUCAGCACCAUAUUGGUGGCCAGUUCUGAGGCUAGCACCACUUCAACAAUUCCUGUUGACUCCAAAACUUUUGUGACCACUGCUAGUGAAGCCAGCUCAUCUCCCACAACUGCUGAAGAUACCAGCAUUGCAACCUCAACUCCUAGUGAAGGAAGCACUCCAUUAACAAGUAUGCCUGUCAGCACCACUCCAGUGGCCAGUUCUGAGGCUAGCAACCUUUCAACAACUCCUGUUGACUCCAAAACUCAGGUGACCACUUCUACUGAAGCCAGUUCAUCUCCUCCAACUGCUGAAGUUAACAGCAUGCCAACCUCAACUCCUAGUGAAGGAAGCACUCCAUUAACAAGUAUGUCUGUCAGCACCAUGCCGGUGGCCAGUUCUGAGGCUAGCACCCUUUCAACAACUCCUGUUGACACCAGCACACCUGUGACCACUUCUAGUGAAGCCAGUUCAUCUUCUACAACUCCUGAAGGUACCAGCAUACCAACCUCAACUCCUAGUGAAGGAAGCACUCCAUUAACAAACAUGCCUGUCAGCACCAGGCUGGUGGUCAGUUCUGAGGCUAGCACCACUUCAACAACUCCUGCUGACUCCAACACUUUUGUGACCACUUCUAGUGAAGCUAGUUCAUCUUCUACAACUGCUGAAGGUACCAGCAUGCCAACCUCAACUUACAGUGAAAGAGGCACUACAAUAACAAGUAUGUCUGUCAGCACCACACUGGUGGCCAGUUCUGAGGCUAGCACCCUUUCAACAACUCCUGUUGACUCCAACACUCCUGUGACCACUUCAACUGAAGCCACUUCAUCUUCUACAACUGCGGAAGGUACCAGCAUGCCAACCUCAACUUAUACUGAAGGAAGCACUCCAUUAACAAGUAUGCCUGUCAACACCACACUGGUGGCCAGUUCUGAGGCUAGCACCCUUUCAACAACUCCUGUUGACACCAGCACACCUGUGACCACUUCAACUGAAGCCAGUUCCUCUCCUACAACUGCUGAUGGUGCCAGUAUGCCAACCUCAACUCCUAGUGAAGGAAGCACUCCAUUAACAAGUAUGCCUGUCAGCAAAACGCUGUUGACCAGUUCUGAGGCUAGCACCCUUUCAACAACUCCUCUUGACACAAGCACACAUAUCACCACUUCUACUGAAGCCAGUUGCUCUCCUACAACCACUGAAGGUACCAGCAUGCCAAUCUCAACUCCUAGUGAAGGAAGUCCUUUAUUAACAAGUAUACCUGUCAGCAUCACACCGGUGACCAGUCCUGAGGCUAGCACCCUUUCAACAACUCCUGUUGACUCCAACAGUCCUGUGACCACUUCUACUGAAGUCAGUUCAUCUCCUACACCUGCUGAAGGUACCAGCAUGCCAACCUCAACUUAUAGUGAAGGAAGAACUCCUUUAACAAGUAUGCCUGUCAGCACCACACUGGUGGCCACUUCUGCAAUCAGCACCCUUUCAACAACUCCUGUUGACACCAGCACACCUGUGACCAAUUCUACUGAAGCCCGUUCGUCUCCUACAACUUCUGAAGGUACCAGCAUGCCAACCUCAACUCCUGGGGAAGGAAGCACUCCAUUAACAAGUAUGCCUGACAGCACCACGCCGGUAGUCAGUUCUGAGGCUAGAACACUUUCAGCAACUCCUGUUGACACCAGCACACCUGUGACCACUUCUACUGAAGCCACUUCAUCUCCUACAACUGCUGAAGGUACCAGCAUACCAACCUCGACUCCUAGUGAAGGAACGACUCCAUUAACAAGCACACCUGUCAGCCACACGCUGGUGGCCAAUUCUGAGGCUAGCACCCUUUCAACAACUCCUGUUGACUCCAACACUCCUUUGACCACUUCUACUGAAGCCAGUUCACCUCCUCCCACUGCUGAAGGUACCAGCAUGCCAACCUCAACUCCUAGUGAAGGAAGCACUCCAUUAACACGUAUGCCUGUCAGCACCACAAUGGUGGCCAGUUCUGAAACGAGCACACUUUCAACAACUCCUGCUGACACCAGCACACCUGUGACCACUUAUUCUCAAGCCAGUUCAUCUUCUACAACUGCUGACGGUACCAGCAUGCCAACCUCAACUUAUAGUGAAGGAAGCACUCCACUAACAAGUGUGCCUGUCAGCACCAGGCUGGUGGUCAGUUCUGAGGCUAGCACCCUUUCCACAACUCCUGUCGACACCAGCAUACCUGUCACCACUUCUACUGAAGCCAGUUCAUCUCCUACAACUGCUGAAGGUACCAGCAUACCAACCUCACCUCCCAGUGAAGGAACCACUCCGUUAGCAAGUAUGCCUGUCAGCACCACGCUGGUGGUCAGUUCUGAGGCUAACACCCUUUCAACAACUCCUGUGGACUCCAAAACUCAGGUGGCCACUUCUACUGAAGCCAGUUCACCUCCUCCAACUGCUGAAGUUACCAGCAUGCCAACCUCAACUCCUGGAGAAAGAAGCACUCCAUUAACAAGUAUGCCUGUCAGACACACGCCAGUGGCCAGUUCUGAGGCUAGCACCCUUUCAACAUCUCCCGUUGACACCAGCACACCUGUGACCACUUCUGCUGAAACCAGUUCCUCUCCUACAACCGCUGAAGGUACCAGCUUGCCAACCUCAACUACUAGUGAAGGAAGUACUCUAUUAACAAGUAUACCUGUCAGCACCACGCUGGUGACCAGUCCUGAGGCUAGCACCCUUUUAACAACUCCUGUUGACACUAAAGGUCCUGUGGUCACUUCUAAUGAAGUCAGUUCAUCUCCUACACCUGCUGAAGGUACCAGCAUGCCAACCUCAACUUAUAGUGAAGGAAGAACUCCUUUAACAAGUAUACCUGUCAACACCACACUGGUGGCCAGUUCUGCAAUCAGCAUCCUUUCAACAACUCCUGUUGACAACAGCACACCUGUGACCACUUCUACUGAAGCCUGUUCAUCUCCUACAACUUCUGAAGGUACCAGCAUGCCAAACUCAAAUCCUAGUGAAGGAACCACUCCGUUAACAAGUAUACCUGUCAGCACCACGCCGGUAGUCAGUUCUGAGGCUAGCACCCUUUCAGCAACUCCUGUUGACACCAGCACCCCUGGGACCACUUCUGCUGAAGCCACUUCAUCUCCUACAACUGCUGAAGGUAUCAGCAUACCAACCUCAACUCCUAGUGAAGGAAAGACUCCAUUAAAAAGUAUACCUGUCAGCAACACGCCGGUGGCCAAUUCUGAGGCUAGCACCCUUUCAACAACUCCUGUUGACUCUAACAGUCCUGUGGUCACUUCUACAGCAGUCAGUUCAUCUCCUACACCUGCUGAAGGUACCAGCAUAGCAAUCUCAACGCCUAGUGAAGGAAGCACUGCAUUAACAAGUAUACCUGUCAGCACCACAACAGUGGCCAGUUCUGAAAUCAACAGCCUUUCAACAACUCCUGCUGUCACCAGCACACCUGUGACCACUUAUUCUCAAGCCAGUUCAUCUCCUACAACUGCUGACGGUACCAGCAUGCAAACCUCAACUUAUAGUGAAGGAAGCACUCCACUAACAAGUUUGCCUGUCAGCACCAUGCUGGUGGUCAGUUCUGAGGCUAACACCCUUUCAACAACCCCUAUUGACUCCAAAACUCAGGUGACCGCUUCUACUGAAGCCAGUUCAUCUACAACCGCUGAAGGUAGCAGCAUGACAAUCUCAACUCCUAGUGAAGGAAGUCCUCUAUUAACAAGUAUACCUGUCAGCACCACGCCGGUGGCCAGUCCUGAGGCUAGCACCCUUUCAACAACUCCUGUUGACUCCAACAGUCCUGUGAUCACUUCUACUGAAGUCAGUUCAUCUCCUACACCUGCUGAAGGUACCAGCAUGCCAACCUCAACUUAUACUGAAGGAAGAACUCCUUUAACAAGUAUAACUGUCAGAACAACACCGGUGGCCAGCUCUGCAAUCAGCACCCUUUCAACAACUCCCGUUGACAACAGCACACCUGUGACCACUUCUACUGAAGCCCGUUCAUCUCCUACAACUUCUGAAGGUACCAGCAUGCCAAACUCAACUCCUAGUGAAGGAACCACUCCAUUAACAAGUAUACCUGUCAGCACCACGCCGGUACUCAGUUCUGAGGCUAGCACCCUUUCAGCAACUCCUAUUGACACCAGCACCCCUGUGACCACUUCUACUGAAGCCACUUCGUCUCCUACAACUGCUGAAGGUACCAGCAUACCAACCUCGACUCUUAGUGAAGGAAUGACUCCAUUAACAAGCACACCUGUCAGCCACACGCUGGUGGCCAAUUCUGAGGCUAGCACCCUUUCAACAACUCCUGUUGACUCUAACAGUCCUGUGGUCACUUCUACAGCAGUCAGUUCAUCUCCUACACCUGCUGAAGGUACCAGCAUAGCAACCUCAACGCCUAGUGAAGGAAGCACUGCAUUAACAAGUAUACCUGUCAGCACCACAACAGUGGCCAGUUCUGAAACCAACACCCUUUCAACAACUCCCGCUGUCACCAGCACACCUGUGACCACUUAUGCUCAAGUCAGUUCAUCUCCUACAACUGCUGACGGUAGCAGCAUGCCAACCUCAACUCCUAGGGAAGGAAGGCCUCCAUUAACAAGUAUACCUGUCAGCACCACAACAGUGGCCAGUUCUGAAAUCAACACCCUUUCAACAACUCUUGCUGACACCAGGACACCUGUGACCACUUAUUCUCAAGCCAGUUCAUCUCCUACAACUGCUGAUGGUACCAGCAUGCCAACCCCAGCUUAUAGUGAAGGAAGCACUCCACUAACAAGUAUGCCUCUCAGCACCACGCUGGUGGUCAGUUCUGAGGCUAGCACUCUUUCCACAACUCCUGUUGACACCAGCACUCCUGCCACCACUUCUACUGAAGGCAGUUCAUCUCCUACAACUGCAGGAGGUACCAGCAUACAAACCUCAACUCCUAGUGAACGGACCACUCCAUUAGCAGGUAUGCCUGUCAGCACUACGCUUGUGGUCAGUUCUGAGGGUAACACCCUUUCAACAACUCCUGUUGACUCCAAAACUCAGGUGACCAAUUCUACUGAAGCCAGUUCAUCUGCAACCGCUGAAGGUAGCAGCAUGACAAUCUCAGCUCCUAGUGAAGGAAGUCCUCUACUAACAAGUAUACCUCUCAGCACCACGCCGGUGGCCAGUCCUGAGGCUAGCACCCUUUCAACAACUCCUGUUGACUCCAACAGUCCUGUGAUCACUUCUACUGAAGUCAGUUCAUCUCCUAUACCUACUGAAGGUACCAGCAUGCAAACCUCAACUUAUAGUGACAGAAGAACUCCUUUAACAAGUAUGCCUGUCAGCACCACAGUGGUGGCCAGUUCUGCAAUCAGCACCCUUUCAACAACUCCUGUUGACACCAGCACACCUGUGACCAAUUCUACUGAAGCCCGUUCAUCUCCUACAACUUCUGAAGGUACCAGCAUGCCAACCUCAACUCCUAGUGAAGGAAGCACUCCAUUCACAAGUAUGCCUGUCAGCACCAUGCCGGUAGUUACUUCUGAGGCUAGCACCCUUUCAGCAACUCCUGUUGACACCAGCACACCUGUGACCACUUCUACUGAAGCCACUUCAUCUCCUACAACUGCUGAAGGUACCAGCAUACCAACUUCAACUCUUAGUGAAGGAACGACUCCAUUAACAAGUAUACCUGUCAGCCACACGCUGGUGGCCAAUUCUGAGGUUAGCACCCUUUCAACAACUCCUGUUGACUCCAACACUCCUUUCACUACUUCUACUGAAGCCAGUUCACCUCCUCCCACUGCUGAAGGUACCAGCAUGCCAACCUCAACUUCUAGUGAAGGAAACACUCCAUUAACACGUAUGCCUGUCAGCACCACAAUGGUGGCCAGUUUUGAAACAAGCACACUUUCUACAACUCCUGCUGACACCAGCACACCUGUGACUACUUAUUCUCAAGCCGGUUCAUCUCCUACAACUGCUGACGAUACUAGCAUGCCAACCUCAACUUAUAGUGAAGGAAGCACUCCACUAACAAGUGUGCCUGUCAGCACCAUGCCGGUGGUCAGUUCUGAGGCUAGCACCCAUUCCACAACUCCUGUUGACACCAGCACACCUGUCACCACUUCUACUGAAGCCAGUUCAUCUCCUACAACUGCUGAAGGUACCAGCAUACCAACCUCACCUCCUAGUGAAGGAACCACUCCGUUAGCAAGUAUGCCUGUCAGCACCACGCCGGUGGUCAGUUCUGAGGCUGGCACCCUUUCCACAACUCCUGUUGACACCAGCACACCUAUGACCACUUCUACUGAAGCCAGUUCAUCUCCUACAACUGCUGAAGAUAUCGUCGUGCCAAUCUCAACUGCUAGUGAAGGAAGUACUCUAUUAACAAGUAUACCUGUCAGCACCACGCCAGUGGCCAGUCCUGAGGCUAGCACCCUUUCAACAACUCCUGUUGACUCCAACAGUCCUGUGGUCACUUCUACUGAAAUCAGUUCAUCUGCUACAUCCGCUGAAGGUACCAGCAUGCCUACCUCAACUUAUAGUGAAGGAAGCACUCCAUUAAGAAGUAUGCCUGUCAGCACCAAGCCGUUGGCCAGUUCUGAGGCUAGCACUCUUUCAACAACUCCUGUUGACACCAGCAUACCUGUCACCACUUCUACUGAAACCAGUUCAUCUCCUACAACUGCAAAAGAUACCAGCAUGCCAAUCUCAACUCCUAGUGAAGUAAGUACUUCAUUAACAAGUAUACUUGUCAGCACCAUGCCAGUGGCCAGUUCUGAGGCUAGCACCCUUUCAACAACUCCUGUUGACACCAGGACACUUGUGACCACUUCCACUGGAACCAGUUCAUCUCCUACAACUGCUGAAGGUAGCAGCAUGCCAACCUCAACUCCUGGUGAAAGAAGCACUCCAUUAACAAAUAUACUUGUCAGCACCACGCUGUUGGCCAAUUCUGAGGCUAGCACCCUUUCAACAACUCCUGUUGACACCAGCACACCUGUCACCACUUCUGCUGAAGCCAGUUCUUCUCCUACAACUGCUGAAGGUACCAGCAUGCGAAUCUCAACUCCUAGUGAUGGAAGUACUCCAUUAACAAGUAUACUUGUCAGCACCCUGCCAGUGGCCAGUUCUGAGGCUAGCACCGUUUCAACAACUGCUGUUGACACCAGCAUACCUGUCACCACUUCUACUGAAGCCAGUUCCUCUCCUACAACUGCUGAAGUUACCAGCAUGCCAACCUCAACUCCUAGUGAAACAAGUACUCCAUUAACUAGUAUGCCUGUCAACCACACGCCAGUGGCCAGUUCUGAGGCUGGCACCCUUUCAACAACUCCUGUUGACACCAGCACACCUGUGACCACUUCUACUAAAGCCAGUUCAUCUCCUACAACUGCUGAAGGUAUCGUCGUGCCAAUCUCAACUGCUAGUGAAGGAAGUACUCUAUUAACAAGUAUACCUGUCAGCACCACGCCGGUGGCCAGUUCUGAGGCUAGCACCCUUUCAACAACUCCUGUUGAUACCAGCAUACCUGUCACCACUUCUACUGAAGGCAGUUCUUCUCCUACAACUGCUGAAGGUACCAGCAUGCCAAUCUCAACUCCUAGUGAAGUAAGUACUCCAUUAACAAGUAUACUUGUCAGCACCGUGCCAGUGGCCGGUUCUGAGGCUAGCACCCUUUCAACAACUCCUGUUGACACCAGGACACCUGUCACCACUUCUGCUGAAGCUAGUUCUUCUCCUACAACUGCUGAAGGUACCAGCAUGCCAAUCUCAACUCCUGGCGAAAGAAGAACUCCAUUAACAAGUAUGUCUGUCAGCACCAUGCCGGUGGCCAGUUCUGAGGCUAGCACCCUUUCAAGAACUCCUGCUGACACCAGCACACCUGUGACCACUUCUACUGAAGCCAGUUCCUCUCCUACAACUGCUGAAGGUACCGGCAUACCAAUCUCAACUCCUAGUGAAGGAAGUACUCCAUUAACAAGUAUACCUGUCAGCACCACGCCAGUGGCCAUUCCUGAGGCUAGCACCCUUUCAACAACUCCUGUUGACUCCAACAGUCCUGUGGUCACUUCUACUGAAGUCAGUUCAUCUCCUACACCUGCUGAAGGUACCAGCAUGCCAAUCUCAACUUAUAGUGAAGGAAGCACUCCAUUAACAGGUGUGCCUGUCAGCACCACACCGGUGACCAGUUCUGCAAUCAGCACCCUUUCAACAACUCCUGUUGACACCAGCACACCUGUGACCACUUCUACUGAAGCCCAUUCAUCUCCUACAACUUCUGAAGGUACCAGCAUGCCAACCUCAACUCCUAGUGAAGGAAGUACUCCAUUAACAUAUAUGCCUGUCAGCACCAUGCUGGUAGUCAGUUCUGAGGAUAGCACCCUUUCAGCAACUCCUGUUGACACCAGCACACCUGUGACCACUUCUACUGAAGCCACUUCAUCUACAACUGCUGAAGGUACCAGCAUUCCAACCUCAACUCCUAGUGAAGGAAUGACUCCAUUAACUAGUGUACCUGUCAGCAACACGCCGGUGGCCAGUUCUGAGGCUAGCAUCCUUUCAACAACUCCUGUUGACUCCAACACUCCUUUGACCACUUCUACUGAAGCCAGUUCAUCUCCUCCCACUGCUGAAGGUACCAGCAUGCCAACCUCAACUCCUAGUGAAGGAAGCACUCCAUUAACAAGUAUGCCUGUCAGCACCACAACGGUGGCCAGUUCUGAAACGAGCACCCUUUCAACAACUCCUGCUGACACCAGCACACCUGUGACCACUUAUUCUCAAGCCAGUUCAUCUCCUCCAAUUGCUGACGGUACUAGCAUGCCAACCUCAACUUAUAGUGAAGGAAGCACUCCACUAACAAAUAUGUCUUUCAGCACCACGCCAGUGGUCAGUUCUGAGGCUAGCACCCUUUCCACAACUCCUGUUGACACCAGCACACCUGUCACCACUUCUACUGAAGCCAGUUUAUCUCCUACAACUGCUGAAGGUACCAGCAUACCAACCUCAAGUCCUAGUGAAGGAACCACUCCAUUAGCAAGUAUGCCUGUCAGCACCACGCCGGUGGUCAGUUCUGAGGUUAACACCCUUUCAACAACUCCUGUGGACUCCAACACUCUGGUGACCACUUCUACUGAAGCCAGUUCAUCUCCUACAAUCGCUGAAGGUACCAGCUUGCCAACCUCAACUACUAGUGAAGGAAGCACUCCAUUAUCAAUUAUGCCUCUCAGUACCACGCCGGUGGCCAGUUCUGAGGCUAGCACCCUUUCAACAACUCCUGUUGACACCAGCACACCUGUGACCACUUCUUCUCCAACCAAUUCAUCUCCUACAACUGCUGAAGUUACCAGCAUGCCAACAUCAACUGCUGGUGAAGGAAGCACUCCAUUAACAAAUAUGCCUGUCAGCACCACACCGGUGGCCAGUUCUGAGGCUAGCACCCUUUCAACAACUCCUGUUGACUCCAACACUUUUGUUACCAGUUCUAGUCAAGCCAGUUCAUCUCCAGCAACUCUUCAGGUCACCACUAUGCGUAUGUCUACUCCAAGUGAAGGAAGCUCUUCAUUAACAACUAUGCUCCUCAGCAGCACAUAUGUGACCAGUUCUGAGGCUAGCACACCUUCCACUCCUUCUGUUGACAGAAGCACACCUGUGACCACUUCUACUCAGAGCAAUUCUACUCCUACACCUCCUGAAGUUAUCACCCUGCCAAUGUCAACUCCUAGUGAAGUAAGCACUCCAUUAACCAUUAUGCCUGUCAGCACCACAUCGGUGACCAUUUCUGAGGCUGGCACAGCUUCAACACUUCCUGUUGACACCAGCACACCUGUGAUCACUUCUACCCAAGUCAGUUCAUCUCCUGUGACUCCUGAAGGUACCACCAUGCCAAUCUGGACGCCUAGUGAAGGAAGCACUCCAUUAACAACUAUGCCUGUCAGCACCACACGUGUGACCAGCUCUGAGGGUAGCACCCUUUCAACACCUUCUGUUGUCACCAGCACACCUGUGACCACUUCUACUGAAGCCAUUUCAUCUUCUGCAACUCUUGACAGCACCACCAUGUCUGUGUCAAUGCCCAUGGAAAUAAGCACCCUUGGGACCACUAUUCUUGUCAGUACCACACCUGUUACGAGGUUUCCUGAGAGUAGCACCCCUUCCAUACCAUCUGUUUACACCAGCAUGUCUAUGACCACUGCCUCUGAAGGCAGUUCAUCUCCUACAACUCUUGAAGGCACCACCACCAUGCCUAUGUCAACUACGAGUGAAAGAAGCACUUUAUUGACAACUGUCCUCAUCAGCCCUAUAUCUGUGAUGAGUCCUUCUGAGGCCAGCACACUUUCAACACCUCCUGGUGAUACCAGCACACCUUUGCUCACCUCUACCAAAGCCGGUUCAUUCUCCAUACCUGCUGAAGUCACUACCAUACGUAUUUCAAUUACCAGUGAAAGAAGCACUCCAUUAACAACUCUCCUUGUCAGCACCACACUUCCAACUAGCUUUCCUGGGGCCAGCAUAGCUUCGACACCUCCUCUUGACACAAGCACAACUUUUACCCCUUCUACUGACACUGCCUCAACUCCCACAAUUCCUGUAGCCACCACCAUAUCUGUAUCAGUGAUCACAGAAGGAAGCACACCUGGGACAACCAUUUUUAUUCCCAGCACUCCUGUCACCAGUUCUACUGCUGAUGUCUUUCCUGCAACAACUGGUGCUGUAUCUACCCCUGUGAUAACUUCCACUGAACUAAACACACCAUCAACCUCCAGUAGUAGUACCACCACAUCUUUUUCAACUACUAAGGAAUUUACAACACCCGCAAUGACUACUGCAGCUCCCCUCACAUAUGUGACCAUGUCUACUGCCCCCAGCACACCCAGAACAACCAGCAGAGGCUGCACUACUUCUGCAUCAACGCUUUCUGCAACCAGUACACCUCACACCUCUACUUCUGUCACCACCCGUCCUGUGACCCCUUCAUCAGAAUCCAGCAGGCCGUCAACAAUUACUUCUCACACCAUCCCACCUACAUUUCCUCCUGCUCACUCCAGUACACCUCCAACAACCUCUGCCUCCUCCACGACUGUGAACCCUGAGGCUGUCACCACCAUGACCACCAGGACAAAACCCAGCACACGGACCACUUCCUUCCCCACGGUGACCACCACCGCUGUCCCCACGAAUACUACAAUUAAGAGCAACCCCACCUCAACUCCUACUGUGCCAAGAACCACAACAUGCUUUGGAGAUGGGUGCCAGAAUACGGCCUCUCGCUGCAAGAAUGGAGGCACCUGGGAUGGGCUCAAGUGCCAGUGUCCCAACCUCUAUUAUGGGGAGUUGUGUGAGGAGGUGGUCAGCAGCAUUGACAUAGGGCCACCGGAGACUAUCUCUGCCCAAAUGGAACUGACUGUGACAGUGACCAGUGUGAAGUUCACCGAAGAGCUAAAAAACCACUCUUCCCAGGAAUUCCAGGAGUUCAAACAGACAUUCACGGAACAGAUGAAUAUUGUGUAUUCCGGGAUCCCUGAGUAUGUCGGGGUGAACAUCACAAAGCUACGUCUUGGCAGUGUGGUGGUGGAGCAUGACGUCCUCCUAAGAACCAAGUACACACCAGAAUACAAGACAGUAUUGGACAAUGCCACCGAAGUAGUGAAAGAGAAAAUCACAAAAGUGACCACACAGCAAAUAAUGAUUAAUGAUAUUUGCUCAGACAUGAUGUGUUUCAACACCACUGGCACCCAAGUGCAAAACAUUACGGUGACCCAGUACGACCCUGAAGAGGACUGCCGGAAGAUGGCCAAGGAAUAUGGAGACUACUUCGUAGUGGAGUACCGGGACCAGAAGCCAUACUGCAUCAGCCCCUGUGAGCCUGGCUUCAGUGUCUCCAAGAACUGUAACCUCGGCAAGUGCCAGAUGUCUCUAAGUGGACCUCAGUGCCUCUGCGUGACCACGGAAACUCACUGGUACAGUGGGGAGACCUGUAACCAGGGCACCCAGAAGAGUCUGGUGUACGGCCUCGUGGGGGCAGGGGUCGUGCUGAUGCUGAUCAUCCUGGUAGCUCUCCUGAUGCUCGUUUUCCGCUCCAAGAGAGAGGUGAAACGGCAAAAGUACAGAUUGUCUCAGUUAUACAAGUGGCAAGAAGAGGACAGUGGACCAGCUCCUGGGACCUUCCAAAACAUUGGCUUUGACAUCUGCCAAGAUGAUGAUUCCAUCCACCUGGAGUCCAUCUAUAGUAAUUUCCAGCCCUCCUUGAGACACAUAGACCCUGAAACAAAGAUCCGAAUUCAGAGGCCUCAGGUAAUGACGACAUCAUUUUAAGGCAUGGAGCUGAGAAGUCUGGGAGUGAGGAGAUCCCAGUCCGGCUAAGCUUGGUGGAGCAUUUUCCCAUUGAGAGCCUUCCAUGGGAACUCAAUGUUCCCAUUGUAAGUACAGGAAACAAGCCCUGUACUUACCAAGGAGAAAGAGGAGAGACAGCAGUGCUGGGAGAUUCUCAAAUAGAAACCCGUGGACGCUCCAAUGGGCUUGUCAUGAUAUCAGGCUAGGCUUUCCUGCUCAUUUUUCAAAGACGCUCCAGAUUUGAGGGUACUCUGACUGCAACAUCUUUCACCCCAUUGAUCGCCAGGAUUGAUUUGGUUGAUCUGGCUGAGCAGGCGGGUGUCCCCGUCCUCCCUCACUGCCCCAUAUGUGUCCCUCCUAAAGCUGCAUGCUCAGUUGAAGAGGACGAGAGGACGACCUUCUCUGAUAGAGGAGGACCACGCUUCAGUCAAAGGCAUACAAGUAUCUAUCUGGACUUCCCUGCUAGCACUUCCAAACAAGCUCAGAGAUGUUCCUCCCCUCAUCUGCCCGGGUUCAGUACCAUGGACAGCGCCCUCGACCCGCUGUUUACAACCAUGACCCCUUGGACACUGGACUGCAUGCACUUUACAUAUCACAAAAUGCUCUCAUAAGAAUUAUUGCAUACCAUCUUCAUGAAAAACACCUGUAUUUAAAUAUAGAGCAUUUACCUUUUGGUAUAUAAGAUUGUGGGUAUUUUUUAAGUUCUUAUUGUUAUGAGUUCUGAUUUUUUCCUUAGUAAAUAUUAUAAUAUAUAUUUGUAGUAACUAAAAAUAAUAAAGCAAUUUUAUUACAAUUUU